GAGGUCACGUGACGGAGCGCCGGAGCGGAGGGAGCCGGGGCUGGGAGUUCUCCUGAGGGAAGAGGAGUGGAGUAGGGGGGACGCGGCGGCGGCGUUGACAAUGAGUUUUCUUGGAGGCUUUUUUGGUCCAAUUUGUGAGAUCGAUAUUGUUCUUAAUGAUGGGGAAACCAGGAAAAUGGCAGAAAUGAAAACUGAAGAUGGCAAAGUAGAAAAACACUAUCUCUUCUAUGACGGAGAAUCCGUUUCAGGAAAGGUACUCUGUAGAGGACUUGAGUACUUUUGGGAUGUGUCUAUGCAUGGUCAGAUAUGUUUAUGACGCCUUCUAUAAGGUUUCACUUUUUUCCCCUUUUCUUUAUCCGGUAAACCUAGCCUUUAAGCAACCUGGAAAGAGGCUAGAACACCAAGGAAUUAGAAUUGAAUUUGUAGGUCAAAUUGAACUUUUCAAUGACAAGAGUAAUACUCAUGAAUUUGUAAACCUAGUGAAAGAACUAGCCUUACCUGGAGAACUGACUCAGAGCAGAAGUUAUGAUUUUGAAUUUAUGCAAGUUGAAAAGCCAUAUGAAUCUUACAUCGGUGCCAAUGUCCGCUUGAGGUAUUUUCUUAAAGUGACAAUAGUGAGAAGACUGACAGAUUUGGUAAAAGAGUAUGAUCUUAUUGUUCACCAGCUUGCCACCUAUCCUGAUGUUAACAACUCUAUUAAGAUGGAAGUGGGCAUUGAAGAUUGUCUACAUAUAGAAUUUGAAUAUAAUAAAUCAAAGUAUCAUUUAAAGGAUGUGAUUGUUGGAAAAAUUUACUUCUUAUUAGUAAGAAUAAAAAUACAACAUAUGGAGUUACAGCUGAUCAAAAAAGAGAUCACAGGAAUUGGACCCAGUACCACAACAGAAACAGAAACAAUCGCCAAAUAUGAAAUAAUGGAUGGUGCACCAGUAAAAGGUGAAUCAAUUCCAAUAAGGCUAUUUUUAGCAGGAUAUGACCCAACUCCAACAAUGAGAGAUGUGAACAAAAAAUUUUCAGUAAGGUACUUUUUGAAUUUAGUGCUUGUUGAUGAGGAAGACCGGAGGUACUUCAAACAGCAGGAGAUAAUUUUAUGGAGAAAAGCUCCUGAAAAACUGAGGAAACAGAGAACAAACUUUCACCAGCGAUUUGAAUCUCCAGAAUCACAGGCAUCUGCCGAACAGCCUGAAAUGUGAACUGAACAGGAGAAAAAAAGAAAAGCAAAAAACUCCUGUAACCCUUGAGAUUAAGUUCAGCAGGUUAAAGAUGGUUGCAGCUGGAGGGGGCGGAAAAAGGCCAAAACUCCAUAUAUGUUAGUCUUCCUUUAUCUUACAGCGCAGCAUUUAUUUUAUGAUAUAAUGAAAUGUUCGUUCAUGUAUAUACAUUUUUAAAAGUGCUUUCUUUGAAACACUGGAACUUUGUUAAGCUGCCUUUUUUUUUUUAACUUCCUACUUUGAUGAUAAGCACUCAGAUAUAUAUCAGCGUAAACAUGAAAAAUUUUCAUGUGAGUAGGCUGGUAUUUGUAAUUUUGCUUUCUUUCUGCAUAAUGUUGAUUAUAAAUCCUCUCUUUUCAGGCUAAUGAUUACCUCUUAUUCUCUACAUGCAAAAAAUUAAAUAUUUUGUGUUCAAAUAAAAUUAGAAAACCUGAGUGGCCUCUUGUGUCCUGCAGAGAUUUAAAACAUGGCAUCUCAAUAUUUUUGAGAACUACAUUUGUUUUUAACAUAUGUGUUUGAGAAAAGCAUAUGGAGUGUUUCACCGCAGGCACUUCUGAGUACCAUUCCAUGGCUUCCAGAAUUUUAUCCUCUUUGAGGUCUUCUGUGCUAUGAAUAUUAGAUUUCUUUCCCCAAGGGAUUAUGUGGCAGGUCAUUAUGGCCUUCUUUUUUUUGGCCAUAUUAAGUAACAGUUUUGCUAUAUUCCAGUAGUACCGUUGUGUGUUUUCUGCAAUGUGGAGUUGACUUAGCUUGGCAUUUUAGAUUUGUUAAAACUAUUUUUUCCAUAAAUACUUUGAAACAUAUUUAUAUAUUUCAAUUUAAGGAAUCUUUUUGCCAUGUGUAUGCAAAUAUUAUUUUCUUCAUACAUUCAUUUUCUUUUCAGGGGAAAAUUUUGGGAUGGGGGACUCAGGAGGACCUGUGAAGCAUGUAGUUAUCUAGAUCUGGGUAAUUUCAUGUUUAUUAAACUCGAACUUUGGCUAGUUAAACUCAUAUUGAAACUUCAUCUAGUCUCUUAAUUUUUUAACACUAAAUUCAAGUCAUUUGUUUUAAGUCUCUAAAAAAGAAGAUUGCAGUCAUCCAUUCAUAUGCAUGGGGUCUGAUCGCAAAUACACUAAAUGUGGAGUGUAGGAACCAAAAUGAAACCUGCUGUAUGGAAACUACUUUCACUUAUGGUUCAUUGGUUUUUGUACCAAUAUUUUUUAUGCACUUCAGUGCAAGUCUUGUCAGUUAACCUUACUUUAUGAGUAAGCUAAAUAACCCAAAUUACAUUUCUUUAAACCUGUUUUACUACUAUGGCACUUUGAUAAAAUGGUCAGGAACCAACUUUACUGGCAAAAGGGUCCAUGUACCACCAUGUGCUGGAGCAUCUGUUCUACAUGUGGAUAUCUAUGAAUGGUAAUGUUUUCCUUCAUGUAAGUGCCUAUUCAGAGUUUCAGAAUUUUAAAAUGCCAAAUAUUUUCAUGGUCAUUUGCAUGUAGUAAGCCAGAAAAUAUUCAAAGAGAUUUUGAAAACCAAUUGUAUUUAACCAGCCUCAAAUUGUGCAACCAUGAUGUAUAAUAAAGAAUUUGAAACAGAAACUGAGCUUGCUGUUUGCAUGAUUAAAAUAGCUCUGUUCUCAAAUCUCUUCUCAUUGUUAGAUUUAUUGUCGAGGAUAGGAUUGUUCAAUAGUUUAGGAAGCUGUAACUGUGAUAAUGAAUUUUUAUAAAUAUUACUGGUUUCAAUUUUAAAUAGAUAUAUAAUGCUUUUAAUAGGCUGGCUUAAAACUGUCAUAUACAGGAUGCCUAUCCGUUUUGCUCAAGACUUUUUGUAGCAUAACCAAUUUGAAAAAAAUUCAAAUUUAAUAUUUGGUGAUUUCAGUCAAAAGUCAGCCAGCUAAUUAGAAGUCAUAAACUGAAAAAGAAAUUUGUGUCUUUAAUGAAGAGUUACAAUGUCUAAUCCAUUGGUUCUCAACCCUGGCUGCAUAUCAGAAUCACCUUAGAAGCUUUUAAAAUAACCAGGCCCGGGUCCUACUCUGACCAAUAAAAUAAGAAUCUCAGAGACUGGGCCAUAAGCAUUAAAAACAAAACAACCUCAAAAAAAUACCUGUCAUCUCAGCCACUUCAGGAGUCUGAGGCGGAAGGAUCACCUGGAAUUCGAGACCAGCCUGGCCAACAAAAAUGAGACCCUAUCUCUACAAAAAAAUUAACAAUGAGCUGGGCAUGGUGGCAUGCACCUGUAUUUCCAGCUAUUUAGGAAGCUGAGACAGGAAGAUCCCUUUGAGAGGUGAAGCCAGCUGGACUUCUGAGUUGCGUGGGGACUUGGAGAACUUUUCUGUCUUACAAGGGGAUUGUAGAAUGCACCAAUCAACACUCUAGCUAGGAUUGUAAAACGCACUCUGGCUAGCUGGAGGUUUGUAAAAUGUACCAAUCAGUGCUUGUGAAAACGCACCAAUCAGGCUGGGCACAGUGGCUCACGCCUGUAAUCCCAGCACUUUGGGAGGCUGAGGCGGGCAGAUCACCUGAGUUCCAGGAGUUCGAGACCAGCCUGACCAACGUGGAGAAACUCCAUCUCUACCAAAAAUGCAUUAGUCGGGCGUGGUGGCACAUGCCUGUAAUCCCAGCUACUAGGGAGGCUGAGGCAGAAUUGCUUGAACCCGGGAGGCAGAGGUUGCAGUGAGCCGAGAUCACACCAAUGCACUCCAGCCUGGCUAGAAGUUUGUAAAAUGGACCAACCAGUGUUCUGUAGAAUGGACCAAUCAGCAGGACGUGGGCGGGGACAAAUAAGAGAAUAAAAGCUGGCCACCCCCCAGCCAGCAGCGGCAACCGGCUCGGGUCCCCCUCCAUACUGUGGAAGCUCUGUUCUUUCACUCUUCACGAUACAUCUUGCUGCUGCUCACUCUGGGCCUGUGCCACAUUUAAGAGCUGUAACACUCAAGGCGAAGGUCCACGGCUCCGUUAAGUCAGCGAGACCGCAAACCCACUGGAAGGAACCAACUCUGGACACACCUUGAGUACACGAAUUUGAAAUUACACUGAGGUGAUCAUGCCACUGCACUGUAGCUUGGGUGACAGAGACACCAUGUCUCAAAAAUCUACCCAGAGUUGGGAACCACUGAUCUAAACCAUUAAAAUUUUUAUUUCUGUCACUAA